GCGCGUUCACGGGCCGUUCCCCCUCACGGGAGUCCUCCGCCCGGGCGUCCGGAACAGUCGACGGCAGACUCCGGCCCGCUGAGCCACCCGAGGGGUCCCGUGGCCUCCGCGGACCCGGAAUCUGGGCCCUCGCGGACCCGCGCCCCGCCCAGUCGCCCCAGCCCCUGCCCCGGGACAGCCUCUCUUCUUCUGCAACAGCCCCUCUUCCCUCGUGACAGCCCGUCCACUGCUCUGUUCGCCAGGGCUUCCCCACACCCACGGAGUGAAGUCAGCCGCGGCCCUGCCUGGGAGGAACUUACCGUCUACCGGGAAAGGUGGCCAGCAGAUGUGUCGGGCCUGGUGAGAGGGUGAGGCGAGACGGCCCGAUCGCCCAGGGCCCCGGAAGCUGCGGAGGUCACCCCCGCCUGGCCUUAGCUCAGGGACACCCUGGAUUCACGUGGGAGCCCCUGCUCCUGCCUCCCCCGUCCCACCACUGAGGCUGUUGGGCCAGGCCAGUCAUGCUAGAACGUAAGUCGUAGGGCAGGGACGGUGGGAGAACUGGGUUAAGAUGCACAGGCCCAGGUCCCCGAGUGUGCCAGGGUUGGGCCUGGAGGCUGUGCUUGUGACCAGUGACCUCCAGGAUCCCAACACCCUGGCUCCUGACUUGGAGAAACCCUGGGCUGGGACUCUGAGGUAGUUAGAGUCAGAGGAAGAGUCUCCACAAGAUGGAGGGCAGCCUGCCAGCCAGGCCCAGGUAGCAUCGCUCCCCUCACCCCUGUACUCCCUCAGGUACUGGAGACUGCUCUUUUUAAUUUUUUAUUUACUAUUAUGUAUAUUUUUUUGAGAUGGAGUUUUGCUCUUGUCGCCCAGUUGGAGUGCAAUGCCGCAAUCUCGGCUCACCGCAACUUCCACCUCCUGGGUUCAAGCAUUUCUCCUGCCUCAGCCUCUGAGUAGCUGGGACUACAGGCAUGCACCAGCACGCCCGGCAAAAAUUUGUAUCUUUAGUAGAGAUGGGGUUUCACCAUGUAGGCCAGGCUGGUCUCGAAGUCUUGACCUCAAGUGAUCCACCCACCUUGCCUCCCGAAGUGCUGGGAUUACAGGCGUGAGCCACCACACCCAGCCGCUCUAUUGUUUUUUAUAAUACUUUGGUGCACCAGCCUCACCAACAUGGUGAAACCACAUCUCUACUAAAAAUAUAAAAAUUAUUCUAGUGUGUUGGCACACGCCUGUAAUCCCAGCUACUCAGGAGGCUGAGGCAAGAGAAUUACUUGAACCUGGGAGUCGGAGGCUGCAGUGGGCCGAGAUCAUACCACUGCACUCCAGCCUGGGCAACAGAGUGAGACCCUGUCUCAAAAACAAACAAACAAACAAUACCUUGGGGCAUAAAGUGUUCCACGGUCCAAUCCAAUUAAAUUUUUUUUUUUUUUUGAGACAGAGUCUCGCUCUGUUGCCCAGGCUGGAGUGCAGUGGCAUGAUCUUGGCUCACUGUAAUCUCUGCCUCCCAGGUUCAAGCAAUUCCCCUGCCUCAGCCUCCCGAGUAGCUGGGACUACAGGCAUGCACCACCACACCCAGCUAAUUUUUGUAUUUUUAGUAGAGAUGGGGUUUCACCAUGUUGGCCAGGCUGGACUCGAACUCCUCACCUCAGGUGAUUUACUCACCUCAGCCUCCUAAAAUGCUGGGAUUACAGGCAUGAGCCACUGUGCCUGGCCAGAUCCAAUUAAUUUUGAGCUCCUUUGACAGGGUGGCUUUUGAGGUCAGUGAGGUUUGUUCUGACAGCAGGCAGGCUCUUCCUAGCUAGCUCUUUCUCCACUUCUCUGUGGUAAACUAGCUGGCCUAUGGUUCAGCUGGUUGCCCUAAUGCGGGUACCAGUCUCUUCUUAAUGGCGCACCACCAAAACUUCCACUGAUUUUGACAGCCCCUUUAAACUUGAACUUCCCUACGCACUGUUUCAAAUCAAGCCAAUUUUCAGGGGGUUGGUGGGUGGGGAGAGCUCUAUUUAUGACCUACGUCUACCCCUAGGCUAAAUCUCUGUCUGAGCCAUGCUGUGGAACUGGGGGCAGGACAGCGGGGCACCUCUCUGAGUGCUGCUAUUGCUUUAGGAGCAGGUCGCUGGGUUGGGCAGGAGCCUCUGGCCUUCUUGGUUGCCCUCUCCCAGUGUGGAGCCUCCUUCCUACAAAUGAGCUGGGGCUCCAUGUUCCCAGCCUGCCGGGCCUGAGAUAUAGCCUCUAUUCUAUGCUUGGGGGCAGGUGGAAGAAAGGAGCCCCUGGCCUGUCUGCCACACUCAGCUGGAAUUUAGCCUCUGCCAUGUGGAGCUGGGAGGGUUGAGAAGUGCUGAGAACCUGGCCCUCCUGGGCAAACACCCUAACCCUUGACGGGGAGCUGGGGGAGAGGGAGCCCUUCUUCUUGGCCACACCUGCCCCCAGUGCUAGGCGGGGGGAGAGGGGUGCUGGAGGUGGGAGGGCAGGAGUGUCAUGGCUCAGGUGCCAACAGGCUUGCCAUUAUUCCCAGGCCUUGGCAGGUUUUCUUGUGUAAACCUUUGUUUGCUGUGUGCCCUGGGCACCAUGCCCAGAGGCUUUCAGUGCUUGCUUUUGAAUAAUCGUCAUCAGUUGUGCUGUUUCACUGGGGCAGGGGUCCACGGAGCUGCACACACUGCCAUUCUGGAAGUGGACACCACUAACUGGGUUUUGGCACGACAGUUAUGAAAAAGAAAGACACUUGAGGGAUUCCGGGUUUUCACUUUGGAAUUGGAGAUAAGGGAUCGUGGGCCCGUGUAGUCUCGGAAGAGGUUGUGUAGUUUAGGAUCAAAGAGCUGGCCGUGAUGAGGGCAGGGAUGCAGGCGCAGCCCGUCUGACUCCAAACUGCCUUGCUCUUAACCCGACUGCAAGACCCUCAAGAACACGGGCCCCAUGGUUUUCCUCUUAUGUUUCUAUCAUCUCUAAAAUACAACAGCCUGGUGGGCAGGUGAGUAUGAAUCUGUCCUCUGCCUUUUCUUGGUAGGUGCUUAUUGCUCCCAUUGCCGUUUAAAGUAGAAUAAGUGUGUGGUAUAGACAUAGCUCUCUUCUGUGGCCUCUUUGGAGCCACAGGGCCAGGUGGUAUCAGAGUGGACAUGCUGCCCUGUACUCAGCCUCUGUCUCUGCCCCCAGGGCCUCCUGCACUGGCCAUGCCCAUGCCCACGGAGGGCACCCCGCCACCUCUGAGUGGCACCCCCAUCCCAGUCCCAGCCUACUUCCGCCACGCAGAACCUGGAUUCUCCCUCAAGAGGCCCAGGGGGCUCAGCCGGAGCCUCCCACCUCCGCCCCCUGCCAAGGGCAGCAUUCCCAUCAGCCGCCUCUUCCCUCCUCGGACCCCAGGCUGGCACCAGCUGCAGCCCCGGCGGGUGUCAUUCCGGGGCGAGGCCUCAGAGACUCUGCAGAGCCCUGGGUAUGACCCAAGCCGGCCAGAGUCCUUCUUCCAGCAGAGCUUCCAGAGGCUCAGCCGCCUGGGCCAUGGCUCCUACGGAGAGGUCUUCAAGGUGCGCUCCAAGGAGGACGGCCGGCUCUAUGCGGUAAAGCGUUCCAUGUCACCAUUCCGGGGCCCCAAGGACCGGGCCCGCAAGUUGGCCGAGGUGGGCAGCCACGAGAAGGUGGGGCAGCACCCAUGCUGCGUGCGGCUGGAGCAGGCCUGGGAGGAGGGCGGCAUCCUGUACCUGCAGACGGAGCUGUGCGGGCCCAGCCUGCAGCAACACUGUGAGGCCUGGGGUGCCAGCCUGCCUGAGGCCCAGGUCUGGGGCUACCUGCGGGACACGCUGCUUGCCCUGGCCCAUCUGCACAGCCAGGGCCUGGUGCACCUUGAUGUCAAGCCUGCCAACAUCUUCCUGGGGCCCCGGGGCCGCUGCAAGCUGGGUGACUUCGGACUGCUGGUGGAGCUGGGUACAGCAGGAGCUGGUGAGGUCCAGGAGGGAGACCCCCGCUACAUGGCCCCCGAGCUGCUGCAGGGCUCCUAUGGGACAGCAGCGGAUGUGUUCAGUCUGGGCCUCACCAUCCUGGAAGUGGCAUGCAACAUGGAGCUGCCCCACGGUGGGGAGGGCUGGCAGCAGCUGCGCCAGGGCUACCUGCCCCCUGAGUUCACUGCCGGUCUGUCUUCCGAGCUGCGUUCUGUCCUUGUCAUGAUGCUGGAGCCAGACCCCAAGCUGCGGGCCACGGCCGAGGCCCUGCUGGCACUGCCUGUGUUGAGGCAGCCGCGGGCCUGGGGUGUGCUGUGGUGCAUGGCAGCGGAGGCCCUGAGCCGAGGGUGGGCCCUGUGGCAGGCCCUGCUUGCCCUGCUCUGCUGGCUCUGGCAUGGGCUGGCUCACCCUGCCAGCUGGCUACAGCCCCUGGGCCCGCCAGCCACCCCGCCUGGCUCACCACCCUGCAGUUUGCUCCUGGACAGCAGCCUCUCCAGCAACUGGGAUGACGACAGCCUAGGGCCUUCACUCUCCCCUGAGGCUGUCCUGGCCCGGACUGUGGGGAGCACCUCCACCCCCCGGAGCAGGUGCACACCCAGGGAUGCCCUGGACCUAAGUGACAUCAACUCAGAGCCUCCUCGGGGCUCCUUCCCCUCCUUUGAGCCUCGGAACCUCCUCAGCCUGUUUGAGGACACCCUAGACCCAACCUGAGCCCCAGACUCUGCCUCUGCACUUUUAACCUUUUAUCCUGUGUCUCUCCCGUCGCCCUUGAAAGCUGGGGCCCCUCGGGAACUCCCAUGGUCUUCUCUGCCUGGCCGUGUCUAAUAAAAAGUAUUUGAACCUUGGGAGCACCCAA